ACUUAAGCUUCGACGCAGGAGGCGGGGCUGCUCAGUCCUCCAGGCGUCGGUACUCAGCGGUGUUGGAACUUCGUUGCUUGCUUGCCUGUGCGCGCGUGCGCGGACAUGGCCUCAAACGAUUAUACCCAACAAGCAACCCAAAGCUAUGGGGCCUACCCCACCCAGCCCGGGCAGGGCUAUUCCCAGCAGAGCAGUCAGCCCUACGGACAGCAGAGUUACAGUGGUUAUAGCCAGUCCACGGACACUUCAGGCUAUGGCCAGAGCAGCUAUUCUUCUUAUGGCCAGAGCCAGAACAGCUAUGGAACUCAGUCAACUCCCCAGGGAUAUGGCUCGACUGGCGGCUAUGGCAGUAGCCAGAGCUCCCAAUCGUCUUACGGGCAGCAGUCCUCCUACCCUGGCUAUGGCCAGCAGCCAGCUCCCAGCAGCACCUCGGGAAGUUACGGUAGCAGUUCUCAGAGCAGCAGCUAUGGGCAGCCCCAGAGUGGGAGCUACAGCCAGCAGCCUAGCUAUGGUGGACAGCAGCAAAGCUAUGGACAGCAGCAAAGCUAUAAUCCCCCUCAGGGCUAUGGACAGCAGAACCAGUACAACAGCAGCAGUGGUGGUGGAGGUGGAGGUGGAGGUGGAGGUAACUAUGGCCAAGAUCAAUCCUCCAUGAGUAGUGGUGGUGGCAGUGGUGGCGGUUAUGGCAAUCAAGACCAGAGUGGUGGAGGUGGCAGCGGUGGCUAUGGACAGCAGGACCGUGGAGGCCGCGGCAGGGGUGGCAGUGGUGGCGGCGGCGGCGGCGGCGGUGGUGGUUACAACCGCAGCAGUGGUGGCUAUGAACCCAGAGGUCGUGGAGGUGGCCGUGGAGGCAGAGGUGGCAUGGGCGGAAGUGACCGUGGUGGCUUCAAUAAAUUUGGUGGCCCUCGGGACCAAGGAUCACGUCAUGACUCCGAACAGGAUAAUUCAGACAACAACACCAUCUUUGUGCAAGGCCUGGGUGAGAAUGUUACAAUUGAGUCUGUGGCUGAUUACUUCAAGCAGAUUGGUAUUAUUAAGACAAACAAGAAAACGGGACAGCCCAUGAUUAAUUUGUACACAGACAGGGAAACUGGCAAGCUGAAGGGAGAGGCAACGGUCUCUUUUGAUGACCCACCUUCAGCUAAAGCAGCUAUUGACUGGUUUGAUGGUAAAGAAUUCUCCGGAAAUCCUAUCAAGGUCUCAUUUGCUACUCGCCGGGCAGACUUUAAUCGGGGUGGUGGCAAUGGUCGUGGAGGCCGAGGGCGAGGAGGACCCAUGGGCCGUGGAGGCUAUGGAGGUGGUGGCAGUGGUGGUGGUGGCCGAGGAGGAUUUCCCAGUGGAGGUGGUGGCGGUGGAGGACAGCAGCGAGCUGGUGACUGGAAGUGUCCUAAUCCCACCUGUGAGAAUAUGAACUUCUCUUGGAGGAAUGAAUGCAACCAGUGUAAGGCCCCUAAACCAGAUGGCCCAGGAGGGGGACCAGGUGGCUCUCACAUGGGGGGUAACUACGGGGAUGAUCGUCGUGGUGGCAGAGGAGGCUAUGAUCGAGGCGGCUACCGGGGCCGCGGCGGGGACCGUGGAGGCUUCCGAGGGGGCCGGGGUGGUGGGGACAGAGGUGGCUUUGGCCCUGGCAAGAUGGAUUCCAGGGGUGAGCACAGACAGGAUCGCAGGGAGAGGCCGUAUUAAUUAGCCUGGCUCCCCAGGUUCUGGAACAGCUUUUUGUCCUGUACCCAGUGUUACCCUCGUUAUUUUGUAACCUUCCAAUUCCUGAUCACCCAAGGGUUUUUUUGUGUCGGACUAUGUAAUUGUAACUAUACCUCUGGUUCCCAUUAAAAGUGACCAUUUUAGUUAAAUUUUGUUCCUCUUCCCCCUUUUCACUUUCCUGGAAGAUCGAUGUCCCGAUCAGGAAGGUAGAGAGUUUUCCUGUUCAGAUUACCCUGCCCAGCAGGAACUGGAAUACAGUGUUCGGGGAGAAGGCCAAAUGAUAUCCUUGAGAGCAGAGAUUAAACUUUUCUGUCAUGGGGAAAGUUGGUGUAUAAAUGAGAAAUGAAGAACAUGGGAUGUCAUGAGUGUUGGCCUAAAUUUGCCCAGCUAUGGGGAAUUUUUCCUUUACCACAUUUAUUUGCAUACUGGUCUUAGUUUAUUUGCAGCAGUUUAUCCCUUUUUAAGAACUCUUUGAUCUUUUGGCCCUUUUAAUGGUGAGGCUCAAACAAACUACAUUUAAAUGGGGCAGUAUUCAGAUUUGACCAUGGUGGAGAGCGCUUAGCCACUCUGGGUCUUUCACAGGAAGGAGAGUAACUGAGUGCUGCAGGAGUUUGUGGAGUGGAGUCAGGAUCUAGGAGGUGAGUGACUCCCUUCCUAGCUGCCCUGGUGAACAGCGCUUGGGUAGAUACCUGCUAUAAGGAGACUGGUCUGGCUGGGUUACUUUCACAUCCUGCCUGUACUCAGAGGGCUUGAGGUCAUUGACAUUAUGAGAUUUUAGGCUUGAUCCCUUUUUGAUUGGAGGGUGGAAGGCCCUCCUAAGGGAAUGAUAAGUGAUAAGAGGGGGAAGGGGUUGCAGCCAAUGAGUUAAAACCUUAGAGCAGUGCUCCUCAGCCUCUUACCAUGUGGUUGUAAACUUGCACGUACCUGCCAACCAGUUAUUUAGCAUGCUUUUUAUUUUAGUUACACAGAGCGUAACAUUAACCCAAGAGCAGAAAGGUUUUAUUUACAGGGUUUUCGAACUUGGUUUGUAAGACAGCUGCCAUCACAAGCAUAGCUUACAAAUGUGCUGGGGACCCCUAAUUGGGAAGUGCUUUCCUCUCAAAUUUUUAUUUUUUAUUUUUAGAGACAGAGUCUUGCUCUGUCAUCCAGGCUGGAGUGCAGUGGCGUGAUCUCGGCUCACUGUAGCCUCUGCCUCCUGAGUUUAAGCGAUUCUCCUGCCUCAGGAGAAUCCCAGCUUCUGAGUAGCUGAGACUACAGGCGUGGGCCACCAUGCCCACCUAGUUUUUGCAUUUUUAGUGGAGGUGUGGUUUCACUGUGUUGGCCAGGCUGGUCUCUUAACUCCUGACCUCAGGUGAUCCACCUGCCUUGGCCUCCCAAAGUGCUGGAAUUACAGGCAUGAGCCGCUGCAUCUGGCCAUCCUCUCAAAUUUUCAAGUGUUCCACAAGUAUGUUCUCUACUGAAGAGUUGCUGCAUCCUUGAAUCUUGGGUGAUUUGAGGCACAGAAACUAUGACUUUAUUUUUUGAGAUGGAGUUUUGCUCUUGUUGCCCAGGCUGGAGUGCAAUGGCACGUUUUUCGGCUUACCGCAACUGCCGCCUCCUGGGUUCAAGCGAUAGCUGGGAUUACAGGCAUGCGCCACCAUGCCCAGCUAAUUUAUUUGUAUUUUUAGUAGAGACGGGGUUUCUCCAUGUUGGUCAGGCUGGUCUCGAACUCCCGACCUCAGGUGAUGUGCACACCUCAGCCUCCCAAUAAACCAUGACUUUUAAGAGGAAUAGCAGGUUUACUUCCCCUGCCAGCAUUGGGGUGCUCUCUAAGCAACAGUAGGCGGAGAGUGGUCUGGCGUAUUAAAAACAAAGGAUCGUCAAGUGGGCCUUCCCAGGCAUUGCUUUGACUUAGUACAUGUAGAGGAUGUGGCAGUUCUCUCCGUCCCUGCCACUGCUGGUUUCUUUGUUAAAUGUUUAGUUGAAAUGGCCUGAUACGAUAUUUGAGUAGUUCACUGUUGGUGCUUUGCCUAGCAGGAUUCUAAUCUUGCUUUGGUUGUGGUCCCCUGAUGCCCUCCUGUUAGGAGUGGAGGAGGUCGAAGCUCCUUGUAAGAUAUGAUUACUGGGACCAUUAGUGUCAAGUUCCUGUGUCCUUCAAAUGGCAUAUGUGAUUGGCCUUGACCUUAAAAGGAAAUAGGGUCCCAGGUGACUGUUUAGUGGGUAGGUCCAGUUUGGGGGGAUCUUCCAGGAGAAUGGAUAGAGACACCUAGCAGCAGAGAGAACAUUGGUGCCUCUCAAGCCAACCUCCCACCUCAGCCUCCCAAGUAGCUGGGACUACAGGUGCUUCCUCGCUACCACACCUGGGUAAUUUUUUUUUUAAUUACUUUUUUUUUUUUAAGAAACAGGGUUUCACUGGGUUGCCCAGGCUGGUCUUGAACUGGCCUCAAGUGACCUGCCUGCCUCAGCCUCCCAAAGUGCUGGGAUCACAGGUGUGACCCACUGCGUUUGGCCAGAAUACUCUAUUCUUACUGAAUGAUUGAAAUCUGUCUUGAAGCAUUAGGUGUCCCAUUUUUGUGAGUUGGAAUUGGGACAGGCUAAGUAGGAAGUGAGGAGGGUGGGGAGAGCUGUGCUGUAGGUCUGUUUGUCCCUUCCUUGAUGUAGCCUUCAGUUAGCCCUUUCAGCUUUUUUCCCCAUCUUGUGCCGGGCCUUCCUGGGUUUCAGUACUUGGAUGUAGGGCUGCAGUUAUGUCAGUGGUGGGUAGAUUGACCAGGAAUUAAGGUCUAGGGUCCAGCCCAUGUGAGACUUGACUCACUGAUCUACCUUUAGGCAUGUCUUCCUUCCAGUCUCAUCCUUUUUAAAUUUUUUUUUUUUUUUUGAGACGGUCUCACUCUCACCCAGGCUGGAUUGCAGUGGUGUGAUCUCGACCAACUGCAACCUCUGCCUCCCACCCGCAAGCUAUCUGCCCACCUCAGCCUCUGGAGUAGCUGGGACGGGACUACAGGCACCUGCCACCAUGACUGGCUAAUUUUUUUUUGUAUUUUUUGUGGAGAUGGGGUCUUGCCAUGUUGCUCAGGCUGGUCUGGUCUCAAAACUGCUCUGGGCUCAAGUGAUUGUCCCACUUUGGCCUCCCAGAGUGCUGGGAUUAAGGUGUGAGAUACUGUGUCCGGCUAUGAAAAUUUUAUUUUUAAUUAACUUGUAUAUAUUUAUGGGGUACAAUGUCCUAUUUCUGUACAUGUACACAUUGUGGAAUCAAAUCAGGCUAAUAUAUCCAUCACUUCAUAUCAUUAGCAUGAAUGAGAACAUACAAAGCCACUCUUAGAAAAUUUUGAAAUUUAUGUUAUUUCAGCCCUUUUAUGCUGGAGGUUGCAAAUGUUUUGUGAAUAAUCAGACCAAAAAUAAAAACAAAAAAUGAUUGACUUCAGUCAUUCAGUAAGAA